AGUAGCGCCUGGUGGCGGUGGCAGUUUGCCCGCGGGUGUGUGAAGGGAGACAGUGUGGAGGCCACAGGGUACUCGCCACGAUGAGCAGCACCUUAGCUAAGAUCGCGGAGAUAGAAGCAGAGAUGGCUCGGACUCAAAAGAACAAGGCCACAGCACACCACUUAGGGCUGCUUAAGGCUCGUCUUGCUAAGCUUCGUCGAGAACUCAUUACUCCAAAGGGUGGUGGUGGUGGAGGUCCAGGAGAAGGUUUUGAUGUGGCCAAGACAGGUGAUGCUCGAAUUGGAUUUGUUGGUUUUCCAUCUGUGGGGAAGUCAACACUGCUUAGUAACCUGGCAGGGGUAUAUUCUGAGGUGGCAGCCUAUGAAUUCACUACUCUGACCACUGUGCCUGGUGUCAUCAGAUACAAAGGUGCCAAGAUCCAGCUCCUGGAUCUCCCAGGUAUCAUUGAAGGUGCCAAGGAUGGGAAAGGUAGAGGUCGUCAAGUCAUUGCAGUGGCCCGAACCUGUAACUUGAUCUUGAUUGUUCUGGAUGUCCUGAAACCUUUGGGACAUAAGAAGAUAAUUGAAAAUGAGCUGGAAGGCUUUGGCAUUCGCUUGAACAGCAAACCCCCCAACAUUGGCUUUAAGAAGAAGGACAAGGGAGGCAUUAAUCUCACAGCCACUUGCCCCCAGAGUGAGCUGGAUGCUGAAACUGUGAAGAGCAUUCUGGCUGAAUACAAGAUUCAUAAUGCCGAUGUGACUCUACGUAGUGAUGCUACAGCUGAUGACCUCAUUGAUGUGGUGGAAGGAAACAGAGUUUAUAUCCCCUGUAUCUAUGUGUUAAAUAAGAUUGACCAAAUCUCCAUUGAGGAAUUGGAUAUCAUCUAUAAGGUGCCUCACUGUGUACCCAUCUCUGCCCAUCACCGCUGGAAUUUUGAUGACCUAUUGGAAAAGAUCUGGGACUAUCUGAAACUAGUGAGAAUUUACACCAAACCCAAAGGCCAGUUACCAGAUUACACAUCCCCAGUGGUGCUUCCUUACUCCAGGACCACAGUGGAGGAUUUCUGCAUGAAGAUUCACAAAAAUCUUAUCAAAGAAUUUAAAUAUGCUCUGGUCUGGGGUCUCUCUGUGAAACACAAUCCUCAGAAAGUGGGUAAAGACCAUACGUUGGAGGAUGAGGAUGUCAUUCAAAUUGUGAAGAAGUGAAACCUUUCCCUUUUCCCAUCUGCCGGACGAACCACAACAGCGUUCCCCAUGAUCAAGCACCCUACCCCAGUUCUUUCUGGUUUUGGCAGUCACUGGAUCAGGAUCCAGGGGAGGGAGAUGGAGGCACCCAAACUGGAACUUCAUUUGUCUUACCUUGGUGUCACCUUGUAUGUCGAACUGCAUAAAAGAUCUGGUAGGCUGGUCAGCUACAUGCAGCUCAUGUGUCAUUGUCAGAAUUUGUUUUGGGAUGGGCUGAAUGAGGAAGGGUAUAUACGGUGAAGCAGCUACAGAAGGGAUCCUUGGGAACUUCAUCUUGAGUGUGAAAUGGAUAAAAAUAUGACAUGCUGCAUCUUACUUGAUGUUUACUUAUGGGAACCCCUUCCAAACUAGAUAUGGCUUUCAGUCCUUUCAAGUAGUCUUUCCCACAUGAUACUGGAGAGAGGAAGGACUUUAUGUAAGUUAAUUGAUCACUCCCCGCAAG